AGGAGAGAGGCCAACGGCCGCCCGGGGCGAGGGGAGCCGGUAGGACGGGACCAGGACUGGCCGACCCGGCCCCGCGCGGGGAAGGGGGCGCCUUCCUCCCACAACACAAAACGAGCCUCGCCAGAGAAGACAAGGGCAGAAAGCACCAUGAGUGGGGGCCCAAUGGGAGGAAGGCCCGGGGGCCGAGGAGCACCAGCGGUUCAGCAGAACAUACCCUCCACCCUCCUCCAGGACCACGAGAACCAGCGACUCUUUGAGAUGCUUGGACGAAAAUGCUUGACGCUGGCCACUGCAGUUGUUCAGCUGUACCUGGCGCUGCCCCCUGGAGCUGAGCACUGGACCAAGGAGCAUUGUGGGGCUGUGUGCUUCGUGAAGGAUAACCCCCAGAAGUCCUACUUCAUCCGCCUUUACGGCCUUCAGGCUGGUCGGCUGCUCUGGGAACAGGAGCUGUACUCACAGCUUGUCUACUCCACCCCCACCCCCUUCUUCCACACCUUCGCUGGAGAUGACUGCCAAGCGGGGCUGAACUUUGCAGACGAGGACGAGGCCCAGGCCUUCCGGGCCCUCGUGCAGGAGAAGAUACAAAAAAGGAAUCAGAGGCAAAGUGGAGACAGACGCCAGCUACCCCCACCACCAACACCAGCCAAUGAAGAGAGAAGAGGAGGGCUCCCACCCCUGCCCCUGCAUCCAGGUGGAGACCAAGGAGGCCCUCCAGUGGGUCCGCUCUCCCUGGGGCUGGCGACAGUGGACAUCCAGAACCCUGACAUCACGAGUUCACGAUACCGUGGGCUCCCAGCACCUGGACCUAGCCCAGCUGAUAAGAAACGCUCAGGGAAGAAGAAGAUCAGCAAAGCUGAUAUUGGUGCACCCAGUGGAUUCAAGCAUGUCAGCCACGUGGGGUGGGACCCCCAGAAUGGAUUUGACGUGAACAACCUCGACCCAGAUCUGCGGAGUCUGUUCUCCAGGGCAGGAAUCAGCGAGGCCCAGCUCACCGACGCCGAGACCUCUAAACUUAUCUACGACUUCAUUGAGGACCAGGGUGGGCUGGAGGCUGUGCGGCAGGAGAUGAGGCGCCAGGAGCCACUUCCGCCGCCCCCACCGCCAUCUCGAGGAGGGAACCAGCUCCCCCGGCCCCCUAUUGUGGGGGGUAACAAGGGUCGUUCUGGUCCACUGCCCCCUGUACCUUUGGGGAUUGCCCCACCCCCACCAACACCCCGGGGACCCCCACCCCCAGGCCGAGGGGGCCCUCCACCACCACCCCCUCCAGCUACUGGACGUUCUGGACCACUGCCCCCUCCACCCCCUGGAGCUGGUGGGCCACCCAUGCCACCACCACCGCCACCACCGCCACCGCCGCCCAGCUCCGGGAAUGGACCAGCCCCUCCCCCACUCCCUCCUGCUCUGGUGCCUGCCGGGGGCCUGGCCCCUGGUGGGGGUCGGGGAGCGCUUUUGGAUCAAAUCCGGCAGGGAAUUCAGCUGAACAAGACCCCUGGGGCCCCAGAGAGCUCAGCGCUGCAGCCACCACCUCAGAGCUCAGAGGGACUGGUGGGGGCCCUGAUGCACGUGAUGCAGAAGAGAAGCAGAGCCAUCCACUCCUCCGGGUCUCGCUCUGUGUCCCAGGCUGGAGUACAGUGGUGCAAUCAUGGCUCAGUGCAGCCUCAACCUCCCAGGCUCAAGCGAUCCUCCCGCCUCAGCUCCCAAAGUAGCUGGGACUACAGGCGUGUGCCACCAUACCUGGCUAAUUUUUGGUGUUUUUUUGGUAGUGAUGAGCUCUCACUACCAAGCUCUCACUACUCUCAUGUUGCCCAGGCUGCUCUGCAACUCCAGGGCUCAAGCGAUCUGCCCCGCCUCAGCCUCCCAGAGUGCUGGGAUUACAGGCAUGAGCCACCAGGCCUGGCUGUUAACCUAAUCUUUUUAUAAUAAUGUUACUAUUACUCUCUUAAUCUGUCAGCAAUACUGUCACUAAUCCAUUAUAUGAUGCAAAUAUUAGUAUCAACCUACUAUAGGAACUUCAUCUUUCGACAAUGAUUUUUUUUUUCUUUUGAGACGGAGUCUUGCUCUGUCACCCAGGCUGGAGUGCAGUGGCGCGAUCUUGGCUAACUGCAGACUCUGCCUCCUGGGUUCAAGCGAUUCUCCUGCCUCAGCCUUCCGAGUAGCUGGGACUACAGGCACGCCACUACGCCCAGCUAAUUUUGAUGUUAUUGUCAUUAACCCCAUUAUGUGUCAAAAAUAUUAGCGUUAACCAGACAGGAAGCAAUAAUAUAUUAUCACACCUUUGCUAAUAUUAUUUAAAUUCACCCUAUUAUGUGAUAAAUAGGUUAACAUUAACCCUUUGUUUGACAAUAUCUCGACUAACCACAUUUUUGACAGCAUAAACUUCAACUCCAACUAGAACUCAGACCCCAACUAUAAUCCCUUUCUUGUCCCAAAUGGAAACUCUAACUUGCCCUCCUCUAGCAUGAGACCUCAGAACCCCAGGGUCCAGUCCUCACCUCCCAGGCCCUAUGAAGCCCCCCACCAACCUCCCAGGGCAUCUUAUCUUUCUCUUUCCCUCCAGACGAAGGGGAGGACCAGGCUGGCGAUGAAGAUGAAGAUGAUGAAUGGGAUGACUGAGUGGCUGAGUUACUUGCUGCCCUGUGCUCCUCCCCGCAGGACAUGGCUCCCCCUCCACCUGCUCUGUGCCCACCCUCCACUCUCCUCUUCCAGGCCCCCAACCCCCCAUUUCUUCCCCACCAACCCCUCCAAUGCUGUUAUCCCUGCCUGGUCCUCACACUCACCCAACAAUCCCAAGGCCCUUUUUAUACAAAAAUUCUCAGUUCUCUUCACUCAAGGAUUUUUAAAGAAAAAUAAAAGAAUUGUCUUUCUGUCUCUCUAUAAA